CACCCUACAGCAGUUCAGGCUGUGUGGUUCGCAGGAAGCAUACACUGGCUUUUUGAUUCUUGCUAGUUCCCAGCUCACAGUUUGGGAGGAUCCAACACCAACCUUUACGUGAAGUGGAGGCCCAAGGACAGUGAGGAGCUGGGUGGUCCCAGCCUGGAGCUGUGCCAGCCUGACAUGGGCUACACUCAGGUCUUUGCUGUCUGGUUCCAGAGCCGAACCUUCUUUCCCCCACGCACAGGAAUCUUUCCUUUCCGGUGACCAGGGCCCUGCAGAUGUCGCCAGGAAAGUGGUGAUCCAGGCAGGACCAGGCUGCACUGAAGGGACAGAGAAAUGGAGGCAAACGACCAUUUUAACUUUACUGGCCUUCCCCCUGCACCUGCUGCCUCAGGACUGAAACCCUCUCCUUCCUCAGGGGAGGGCCUCUACACUAACGGGUCUCCCAUGAACUUCCCCCAGCAAGGGAAAAGUUUGAAUGGGGAUGUGAAUGUUAAUGGCUUAUCUACUGUAUCUCACACUACUACUUCAGGGAUUUUGAACUCUGCUCCCCACUCCUCCAGCACCUCACACCUCCAUCACCCCAGCGUGGCCUACGACUGUCUCUGGAACUACUCACAGUACCCAUCUGCCAAUCCUGGCAGCAACCUCAAGGACCCACCCCUUCUCUCCCAGUUCUCGGGGGGACAAUACCCACUCAACGGCAUCCUUGGGGGCAGCCGGCAACCUUCAUCCCCAAGUCAUAACACUAACCUUCGGGCUGGGAGCCAAGAGUUCUGGGCCAACGGUACCCAGAGUCCCAUGGGGCUUAACUUUGAUUCACAAGAACUGUAUGAUUCCUUUCCUGACCAGAAUUUUGAGGAGGUAGGCAGUGGUAUCCAUCCUGAUGAGGCAGCAGAAAAGGAGAUGACUUCAGUUGUGGCAGAGAAUGGCACUGGCUUGGUAGGCAGCUUGGAGCUGGAAGAAGAGCAGCCAGAACUGAAGAUGUGUGGCUACAAUGGCUCUGUCCCUUCUGUGGAAUCGUUACACCAAGAGGUCUCAGUCCUGGUCCCUGACCCCACAGUGAGCUGUUUAGAUGAUCCUUCACAUCUUCCUGAUCAACUGGAAGACACUCCAAUCCUCAGUGAAGACUCUCUGGAGCCCUUCAACUCUCUGGCACCAGAGCCAGUGAGUGGAGGACUAUAUGGUAUUGAUGACACGGAGCUGAUGGGUGCAGAGGACAAGCUGCCUCUUGAGGACAGCCCUGUGAUUUCUGCCCUUGAUUGCCCUUCCCUCAAUAAUGCUACUGCCUUCAGUCUCCUGGCAGAUGAUAGUCAAACAUCAACCUCUAUCUUUGCCAGUCCCACCUCUCCACCUGUCCUAGGGGAGUCUGUCCUGCAAGAUAACAGCUUUGACCUGAAUAAUGGUAGUGACGCUGAACAGGAAGAAAUGGAAACUCAAUCUUCAGACUUCCCACCAUCCCUGACCCAGCCAGCUCCUGAUCAGUCAUCCACUAUUCAGCUACAUCCAGCAACCUCACCAGCAGUCUCGCCAACAACCUCCCCAGCAGUCUCCCUAGUGGUUUCUCCAGCAGCCUCCCCAGAAAUCUCUCCAGAAGUUUGUCCCGCAGCUUCUACAGUUGUCUCUCCAGCAGUCUUCUCAGUGGUCUCUCCAGCUUCCUCAGCAGUCCUCCCAGCAGUCUCCUUAGAAGUCCCGUUGACGGCUUCAGUGACAUCCCCAAAAGCCUCUCCCGUAACUUCCCCAGCAGCUGCCUUUCCAACAGCCUCCCCAGCAAAUAAGGAUGUCAGCAGCUUUCUAGAAACCACUGCUGACGUGGAAGAGAUCACUGGAGAAGGACUCACUGCUUCUGGUAGUGGUGAUGUCAUGAGGAGACGUAUUGCUACCCCAGAAGAAGUUCGUCUUCCCCUCCAACAUGGGUGGCGGAGAGAGGUGCGCAUCAAGAAGGGCAGCCACCGAUGGCAGGGGGAGACCUGGUAUUAUGGCCCCUGUGGGAAGAGGAUGAAGCAAUUUCCAGAAGUGAUCAAGUACCUGAGCCGCAACGUGGUACACAGUGUCCGCCGAGAGCACUUCAGCUUCAGUCCCCGUAUGCCUGUUGGAGAUUUCUUUGAAGAAAGAGACACGCCAGAGGGCUUGCAGUGGGUGCAGCUCUCAGCAGAGGAGAUCCCGUCGAGGAUUCAGGCAAUUACUGGCAAACGGGGUCGACCUCGAAACACUGAGAAGGCUAAGACUAAGGAAGUCCCCAAGGUGAAACGGGGUCGAGGUCGGCCACCUAAGGUCAAAAUCACUGAGCUAUUGAACAAGACAGACAACCGCCCCCUAAAGAAACUGGAGGCCCAAGAAACAUUGAAUGAGGAGGAUAAAGCAAAGAUUGCUAAAAGCAAGAAGAAGAUGAGGCAGAAGGUUCAACGGGGAGAGUGUCAGACUACUAUCCAAGGGCAGGCCAGAAAUAAGCGGAAACAAGAGACCAAGAGCUUAAAGCAGAAGGAAGCUAAGAAGAAAUCCAAGGCUGAGAAAGAAAAAGGAAAGACAAAGCAGGAAAAACUGAAGGAAAAAGUCAAGAGGGAAAAGAAGGAGAAGGUAAAAAUGAAGGAAAAGGAGGAGGUGACCAAAGCCAAGCCAGCCUGUAAAGCAGAUAAGACCCUGGCCACACAGAGGCGCUUGGAGGAACGGCAGAGGCAGCAGAUGAUCUUGGAGGAAAUGAAGAAGCCGACAGAGGAUAUGUGUCUGACUGACCACCAGCCCCUGCCUGACUUCUCACGAGUCCCUGGUCUGACAUUGCCCAGUGGAGCCUUCUCAGACUGCUUGACCAUUGUGGAGUUCCUGCAUAGCUUUGGCAAGGUGCUGGGCUUUGAUCCUGCCAAAGAUGUGCCUAGCCUGGGGGUCCUGCAGGAGGGACUCCUGUGUCAAGGUGACAGCUUGGGUGAGGUGCAAGACCUGCUGGUCAGGCUGCUGAAGGCUGCACUCCAUGAUCCUGGCUUUCCCUCCUACUGUCAGUCCCUAAAGAUCUUGGGGGAGAAGGUGUCUGAGAUCCCACUGACAAGAGACAAUGUGUCAGAGAUCCUGCGCUGCUUCCUUAUGGCAUAUGGAGUAGAGCCAGCCCUCUGUGACCGCCUGCGCACCCAGCCUUUUCAGGCCCAGCCACCCCAGCAGAAGGCUGCUGUCCUGGCCUUCCUUGUGCAUGAGCUCAAUGGCUCCACCCUCAUCAUCAAUGAGAUUGACAAGACUCUGGAGAGUAUGUCCAGCUACAGGAAAAACAAGUGGAUUGUUGAAGGCCGGCUCCGGAGGCUGAAAACUGUUCUGGCCAAGCGAACUGGGCGGUCUGAAGUAGAGAUGGAAGGGCCAGAGGAAUGCCUGGGACGGAGGCGCAGUUCUCGGAUCAUGGAGGAGACCAGUGGCAUGGAAGAAGAGGAAGAAGAGGAGUCUAUAGCAGCUGUCCCUGGCCGCAGGGGUCGAAGAGAUGGAGAGGUUGAUGCCACAGCAUCUAGCAUCCCAGAGCUAGAGCGCCAGAUAGAAAAACUCAGCAAGCGUCAGCUUUUCUUUCGCAAAAAGCUGCUUCACUCAUCCCAGAUGCUUCGGGCGGUCUCCCUGGGUCAGGACCGCUACAGACGUCGCUACUGGGUAUUGCCGUAUUUGGCUGGUAUCUUUGUAGAAGGAACAGAGGGGAACUUAGUUCCUGAGGAGGUGAUAAAGAAGGAAACUGACUCCUUAAAAGUGGCAGCCCAUGCGUCACUCAACCCUGCCCUCUUCUCUAUGAAGAUGGAGUUAGCUGGCUCCAACACCACUGCCAGUUCUCCUGCCCGGGCCCGAGGCCGACCUCGAAAAACUAAGCCCGGGUCUAUGCAACCUAGGCAUCUUAAGUCCCCUGUCAGGGGUCAGGAUUCAGAACAGCCCCAGGCCCAGCUUCAGCCUGAGGCUCAGCUUCAUGCUCCUGCCCAGCCCCAGCCUCAGCUUCAGCUUCAGCUUCAGUCCCAUAAGGGGUUCCUGGAGCAAGAAGGCUCCCCUUUGUCACUGGGUCAGAGCCAGCAUGACCUCAGCCAGUCAGCCUUCCUGUCUUGGCUGAGCCAGACUCAGAGCCAUAGCUCCCUGUUGAGCAGCUCAGUCCUCACACCUGAUAGCAGUCCGGGAAAACUAGACCCAGCUCCAUCACAACCCCCGGAGGAGCCAGAGCCUGAUGAGGCAGAAUCCAGCCCUGAUCCUCAAGCACUCUGGUUUAACAUCUCAGCCCAGAUGCCCUGCAAUGCUGCCCCCACACCGCCCCCUGCAGUUUCUGAGGACCAACCCACUCCCUCCCCUCAGCAGCUUGCCUCCUCCAAGCCAAUGAAUAGACCUAGUGCUGCCAACCCUUGUUCUCCAGUGCAGUUCUCUUCCACGCCCUUGGCUGGGUUGGCCCCUAAGAGGCGAGCAGGAGACCCUGGAGAAAUGCCACAGAGUCCCACAGGGCUGGGACAGCCCAAACGGAGAGGGAGACCUCCCAGUAAGUUCUUCAAACAGAUGGAACAGCGUUACCUAACCCAGCUGACAGCCCAGCCUGUCCCACCUGAGAUGUGCUCAGGCUGGUGGUGGAUACGAGAUCCUGAGAUGUUGGAUGCCAUGCUCAAGGCCCUACACCCCCGAGGUAUCCGGGAGAAGGCACUUCACAAACACCUUAACAAGCACAGGGACUUCUUGCAGGAAGUCUGCCUGCGGCCCUCAGCUGACCCCAUCUUUGAGCCCAGGCAACUACCUGCCUUUCAAGAAGGGAUUAUGAGCUGGUCCCCCAAAGAGAAGACAUACGAGACAGACCUAGCAGUGCUUCAAUGGGUAGAGGAGCUGGAGCAGCGGGUUAUCAUGUCUGAUCUGCAGAUUCGGGGCUGGACAUGUCCUAGCCCAGACUCUACCCGUGAAGACUUGGCCUACUGUGAGCACCUCUCCGACUCCCAGGAGGAUAUCACCUGGCGAGGUCGGGGCAGGGAGGGACUGGCACCUCAGCGUAAAACUACCAACCCUUUGGACCUGGCUGUGAUGCGGCUGGCUGCCCUGGAACAGAAUGUAGAACGGCGGUACCUGCGGGAGCCCCUCUGGCCAACUCAUGAGGUUGUGCUGGAGAAGGCCCUGCUUAGCACACCUAAUGGUGCCCCUGAGGGCACCACUACAGAGAUAUCAUAUGAGAUCACCCCUCGCAUUCGUGUCUGGCGCCAGACCCUCGAGCGGUGCCGGAGCGCAGCCCAGGUGUGCUUGUGCCUGGGCCAGCUGGAGAGGUCCAUUGCCUGGGAGAAGUCUGUCAACAAAGUGACAUGUCUAGUCUGCCGGAAGGGUGACAAUGAUGAGUUUCUUCUGCUUUGUGAUGGGUGUGACCGUGGCUGCCACAUUUACUGCCAUCGUCCCAAGAUGGAGGCUGUCCCAGAAGGAGAUUGGUUCUGUACUGUCUGUUUGGCUCAGCAGGUGGAGGGAGAAUUCACUCAGAAGCCUGGUUUCCCAAAGCGUGGCCAGAAGCGGAAAAGUGGUUAUUCGCUGAACUUCUCAGAGGGUGAUGGCCGCCGACGCCGGGUACUGUUGAGGGGCCGAGAAAGCCCAGCAGCAGGGCCUCGGUACUCGGAAGAAGGGCUCUCCCCCUCCAAGCGGCGGCGACUCUCUAUGCGGAACCACCACAGUGAUCUCACAUUUUGCGAGAUUAUCCUGAUGGAGAUGGAGUCCCAUGAUGCAGCCUGGCCUUUCCUAGAGCCUGUGAACCCACGUUUGGUGAGUGGGUACCGGCGCAUCAUCAAAAAUCCUAUGGAUUUUUCCACCAUGCGGGAGCGGCUGCUCAGGGGAGGGUACACCAGCUCAGAGGAGUUUGCGGCUGAUGCCCUCCUGGUAUUUGACAACUGCCAGACUUUCAACGAGGAUGACUCUGAAGUAGGCAAGGCUGGGCACAUCAUGCGCCGCUUCUUCGAGAGCCGCUGGGAGGAGUUUUAUCAGGGAAAACAGGCCAAUCUGUGAGGCAAGGGAGGUGGGGAGUCACCUUGUGGCAUCUCCCCCCACCUUCCAAACAAAAACCUGCCAUUUUCACCUGCUGAUGCUGCCCUGGGUCCAGACUCAAGUCAGAUACAACCCUGAUUUUUGACCUUGCCCUUGGCAGUGCCCCACAUCCUCUUAUUCCUACAUCCCUUUCUCCCUUCCCUCCUCUUGCUCCUCAAGUAAGAGGUGCAGAGAUGAGGUCCUUCUGGACUAAAAGCCAAAAAAAGAAAGAAAAAAAUAAUUUUUCUUUUCUGUUUUAUUUGCUAAUUAAAAAUGGGGAGGGGGAAAGUCGUCCCUACUUCCUCCUCCCUGCUUCCUCUCCUCCCCUGUACGUGCCCCAGCAUUCUGGGGUUAUUUAACAAUAGCAAUAGUUCUAGUGAAUGUGUGAAACCAAGAAACACUCUGUACUGUGUGCGGACCCGCAGUGACGGCCAGUAAAGUGGACUUAACUCCCAAGUGUGUCGCGCCGGACACCGGGCCCUGGACAUGCUGCUUCCAUGUUCAGUCCCUUCCCUGCUUCUCGCUGUCUUUCUUUUCCCACCUCCCACCCCCCAGUUUUCAGAUUUUCUCUCAUCCAAUAAUGUAAAACUAUCGUGUACGGGUUCCUCCCUCCUUUUCUCUUCUCCCAAAUCUUUUCCCUUCAAAGGAAAAAAAAAUGUUCAGAGGUCCCUGUCUUCUGUCCCCAUCUUCCUGCCGAUAGCUAUCCCCUGUAUGAUGUUGGAUGCUCCUCACAUGCUGAGUUUCCAGCCUUUUCUGAAACUCAGUAGCUGGGGAGAGGGCAGGGAGGCUUCCUGGGCCUUCCAGCCUCCUUCCCCACCUCCUUCCCAAACCCUCUUGGGAACUCCUCAGGGACAACUACUGCUGAGUUUGGGUGCACCCUAAGAUGGAGGCCAGGUAGCAAUGGGGCCGGCCUCAGAGAGAGCGCUGUGUGUGUGUGUGUGUGUGUGUGUGUGUGUGUGUGUCGGCCUCAGAGCGCGCUGUGUGUGUGUGUGUGUGUGUCAGCCUCAGAGCGCGCGCUGUGUGUGUGUGUGUGUGUGCGUGCUUGUGACCCUGUAUUGUUUGAUAGGAUCCAUUCAGUUUCCCCAAGUACCUGUUUUCAUUCCCAUUUUUCCCAUUGUUUAAAACCAUCACUUUUUUGUCUUUGGGAAACCACAGGAACAAUUUCUCUGGAGACAAGGCUGUGUCUCUCUCCUGGUCAUUUUUGUUCCAGCCUCUUCAGACUGUGCAAUCUUUCAGCAGGAACUCCCUCUCUUCUCGGUAGCUUUGAAUCUUAAGCUUCUACGGGAGAGUGGUAGAACUGGAUCAUUUCCUAAUCCCAUUUAGUUGUGCUUUUCUUCAUUUACUUCAUACCCCAGGACCCCUUCCCCAGCAGCAGAGACCCUGGAGCACAGGAGAGUAGGGAGGAGGGGUUCUGGGUCCAUCACUGCCCUACAUGUGACUAUGUCCAAGUUAAGCCCCCAACACGAGAGGAAAGCUGCUGACUCCCAGCUAUAGCCAUGGGCACUUGGCCCCCUGCUUUUCCUGCUCAGCAGAGCCCCUCCCUUCAGAGAUUACGGGUACUUGCACUGGGGAGGUGGCUGCUGGCUGGCCCAAGCAGAGAGCUGAGGCAUCCAAGAAAUGUUCCAUUGGGGGGUGGGGGUGCCAGGUGAGGUGGAGCAUUCCUUGUAUUCUGGCAGCACUGAAGAGCCACUGAAGGGGGUAGGGGCAGUGUAGGUCCUGGGGCAGCCCCUUUAUUCCUUUAUGCCCCUUCUCCCUCAUAGCCUAUUUCUAAAGUCGCCUUUUCUGUCAGAUAAACCUCAAAACUUUUAAUUUUAUUUGAGAUUUUUUUUUGCUUUUAAGAGGUGGAUUGAAGAAUAUUUGAAUUGACUUUAUAUUAUGCAUAAAUAUUUAUAUUUUAUCUAAAUAACUGCGCUGUAACAAACUUUGUGUUAGACAGUUGAAACUGUUAGAGUUGGGGGCUCUGCUUUUUCCCCCUGGCAAUUUUCCCCUGGUAUAAGAUGUGCUAGAUUAAUUUCAUUGUGAGGUGGAUGGGGGAGUGAAAUUGUGAGGUGGAUGGGGGAGUGAAAUCUCCAUGGUUCCUGCUUUGUGUUCCUCUCCCAGCUCCAUCUCUUUCCCUAGGGACCAGGCACUCAUAUGGCGGGGUGGGGUCCUAGCCUCAGUUUGAAGAAGUGGGGGCUGGAGCGGGGUUGGGGGUGGUAGGGAUAGGGCAUGAUCAAAGGGGCCAUUUCUUGCUUUUCUUUCCUCAUCUUCACUGCCCCCUUGAGCUAGGUGGAUUUUCUCUUCAUGACAAGAGUAUUUGGUAGGGAAAGCAGGUUUAAAAUAAAAAGACAACCCACCCCCUGCCCUUUUGCUUCCCUCCCAUCAGUCUGGUUGACAGGAAGAAACCACACCAUCAACACCAACAAGUUUCUGUGUUCCUUUUACAGCAAAAGGGACUUUUUAUAUAACCAAAUGUGGUGUUUUAGUGACUUUUUGAUAAUGUACAGUUUUUUGUGAAUUUAAAUUUAUUUCUUUCUAUAUUUUUAGGACCAAUCUCAUUUUUAAUAAGGUUAAAAAGAAAAAAAAAGUCUAGCGAAAAAACUCCUGUUUUUGCCAUGUGAUGUUCCACAAGUGCAGCUGUAGAAAAGUGCUUGUCAGUUGUUGAAUAAAAAAAACCACAUUUGAUAGAGAUUCAAAAGACUCUGUGUAUUCAUCUUCCCUUCUACACACCUGAGGGGGAGACGGCGUUGGGAUAGGUAUGACUGGCUUAAGAGACCACAGGCAAGGGAACAACAGGGGCUCCUGUUCCAUACCCUCUGUGUGGAUGGAAAGGGUCAUUAGUGCUCCUGCCUAAAUGUCUGGCUGAGUUGCUGGAGCAAAGGGGGAUUCAGUGCAUCCAGGUCCUGCCUUGUGAGAUGUGGCCCCAGCUUCCUAAGCUGCCACCUCUGUGUUCCUGUCAUAGCAAAUAUGGGACCAUCACCAGCUUACCACUUCCCACUCACGGAUAAGACACCAAGACGUAGAC